AGAACGCCGCCUCCUCCGCUUGCGGCCGGUCUGCACCAUGCUGCGAACGUCCGUCCUCCGCCUGCUAGGACGCACGGGGGCUAGUAGGCUGUCUCUCCUGGAGGACUUCGGCCCACGCUACUACAGUUCGGGCUCCCUCAGUGCCGGCGAUGAUGCUUGUGAUGUGCGCGCCUACUUCACUACACCCAUUUUCUACGUGAACGCGGCGCCGCACAUCGGGCACCUGUACUCGGCACUACUGGCGGACGCCCUAUGCCGCCACCGUCGCCUCCGAGGUCCCAGCACGGCCGCCACGCGAUUCUCCACUGGUACCGACGAGCACGGGCUGAAGAUUCAGCAGGCAGCAGCUACCGCGGGCCUGGCCCCGACCGAGCUGUGCGACCGAGUCUCUGAGCAGUUCCAGCAGCUUUUCCAGGAGGCCGGUAUCUCCUGCACAGAUUUCAUCCGCACCACGGAGGCCCGGCACCGGGUGGCUGUGCAGCACUUCUGGGGGGUGCUUAAGUCCCGCGGUCUGCUCUACAAGGGCGUCUAUGAAGGUUGGUAUUGCGCUUCCGACGAGUGCUUCCUGCCUGAGGCCAAGGUCACCCAGCAGCCGGGCCCAUCGGGGGAUUCGUUUCCUGUAUCUCUCGAGAGCGGGCAUCCAGUCUCCUGGACCAAGGAAGAAAACUACAUUUUCAGGCUUUCCCAGUUCCGGAAGCCACUCCAGCGGUGGCUGCGGGGCAACCCUCAGGCGAUCACCCCCGAACCAUUUCAUCACGUAGUUCUUCAGUGGCUGGACGAGGAGCUGCCCGACCUGUCCGUGUCUCGCAGAAGUAGCCACUUGCACUGGGGCAUUCCGGUGCCCGGGGAUGAUUCGCAGACCAUCUAUGUAUGGCUGGAUGCCCUGGUCAACUACCUCACUGUAAUUGGCUACCCAAAUGCUGAGUUCAAAUCUUGGUGGCCGGCCACCUCUCAUAUCAUAGGUAAGGACAUUCUCAAAUUCCAUGCCAUCUAUUGGCCUGCCUUCCUGUUAGGGGCCGGCAUGAGCCCGCCACAGCGCAUCUGUGUCCAUUCCCACUGGACAGUCUGUGGCCAAAAGAUGUCCAAGAGCUUGGGCAACGUGGUGGAUCCUAGGACUUGCCUUAACCGCUAUACCGUGGAUGGCUUCCGCUACUUUCUCCUUCGGCAGGGCGUCCCCAACUGGGACUGUGACUACUAUGAUGAAAAGGUGGUUAAGUUGCUGAACUCCGAGCUGGCAGAUGCCUUGGGAGGUCUCUUGAACCGAUGCACUGCCAAAAGAAUAAAUCCUUCUGAGACCUACCCAGCCUUCUGCACUACCUGCUUCCCUAGUGAGCCAGGGUUGGUGGGGCCGUCAGUUCGUGCUCAGGCAGAGGAUUAUGCUCUGGUGAGCGCAGUGGCCACUUUGCCAAAGCAGGUAGCAGACCACUAUGAUAACUUUCGGAUAUAUAAGGCUCUGGAGGCCGUGUCCAGCUGUGUCCGGCAAACUAAUGGUUUUGUCCAAAGGCAUGCACCAUGGAAGCUGAACUGGGAGAGCCCAGUGGAUGCUCCCUGGCUGGGUACUGUGCUUCAUGUGGCCUUGGAAUGUUUGCGAGUCUUUGGGACUUUGCUGCAGCCUGUCACCCCAAGCCUAGCUGACAAGCUGCUGUCUAGGCUGGGGGUCUCUGCCUCAGAGAGGAGUCUUGGAGAGCUCUAUUUCUUGCCUCGAUUCUAUGGACAUCCAUGCCCUUUUGAAGGGAGGAGGCUGGGACCUGAAACUGGGCUUUUGUUUCCAAGACUAGACCAGUCCAGGACUUGGCUGGUGAAAGCCCACCGGACCUAGAAACUCAGUUCUUACCGGCUUGUGGUAAAAAAGCAAAUGUGUUAUCUUUUUAUUUUUUAUUUUCAGGAAAGUUAUACUAGUAUUUUCUUAAGUGUGGAAUCAAAUGAGCACAUAAGCUGUGUCCCUGUGAAAAGAGGUUUGUAGCCUUUCAGGUGCCUGCUCCUAUUCAUUUCUCUGUGACCAUUGAUCACUGUCCUUUGUGCAUUGUGUGUCUAAGAUGUCUUCAGGGGAAAGAUGGGUAAGAGACAGUGUUGCUAAUGCUGUUCCUUCUUUGUGCCUCCUUCCAAACCACAGUUAUUUGCCCAAACUACCUCUCGUGGCUGGUUUUUCAUUGGCCUGGCCUCUGCUUCUCAGGCUAAUUAGUGACUCCUUUCUUUGAGGGUCAGGGUUGGAGGCCCCUUACUGGUGGUUUUACAGGGGGAUCCUACUUUGUUACACAUGUUGGGUUUCCUGAUAAAAAGAGAGUAUUUUAUUAAACCCUUGAACCAGUGUCCUAGACCAGAUGAUUUUUGCCCAUGUGUAUCCCCAUUUAAAUUCCUACAACUAAGUCUCCCUGCUUUGUUAAUAGUCCAACAGUUGGGUUGUGUAACAUCACACUUCAACCGGUAGAUGGCUCUAAUCUCACACAUUUACUUACUAAAGAUUGAGGAUUCGGAAUAUUUAGAAUAAAUUAGUUUUCUGCUUUCUAAUUUUGCAGAUCUUUACAUUUUUAUUGCUUUUCUUAAAAUAAGGGAUAGCUUUGCAACCACUAUUGUUUUAAUGGAAAGCAAAAAACCCCCCCAAACUUAUCAGAAUCCUCGUUCUUUUUCAGACUACUGAAAAAUGACAUUUACUCUGUUAAAUGUUUAAUAAGUGAAUAAGUAAAUGUAUCAAGUUGUUUAUAUAAUAAAUUAUAAAACUCUUGAGGCACUUGGUAUGUUAAAAAUUUUAAACUUUAGUAACAUUAGGUUACAGGUAUGAUUUAAAAAUUUGUAAAUAGUUCAAAAGGGCAAUGUUUUCUUUAUAUUUCUUAUAGUCUUAAUUUUGUUAUCCAUGUGCAUAAUUUACCUCAUGAUUUCUUUUGGUCAAUCAGGAUCUUUAAUACAAUAUAGAAAUUGUGUAAUAGUUAUUAUAAAUGUUAAUACACAACUUUCAGGUAAUUUUAACUGAUUAUUUCUUUUGCUCUUUUAACUUAAGUUAUUAAAGUUUAAAAGUUCGUAAGUACCUUA